ACACGCUGGGCAGCUGCUGUGCUUGUGUCUCCUCCACCCUGAGAGUCCGAUCCAGCCAAGAUCCGGACGCAGUUGGAGUGUGUCCCAGACCUUUGUCCUCUCGCUGGGCGAAAGCUUGUCUUCAUCAUUAACAAGUUAUUCAGCACUGAUAGUAUGACACAAAACAUGGGAAAUUUCCUUCUGGAGAAUGACUGGACUCUUGUGUCUUCAUGAGAUCCCAGCCCUAGAGCUGAAGCCAUACUUAGCUCUGCUUUUCUAAUGGGUUCUCCUAUGCUCAGUCUCAGGCUGUGCCUGAUACAUCCUUACACUUUGGAGAAGCAGCAAGAAAGUUGAUUCUCGCUAUUUGCUGUUGCUGAACACAGAGCAUGAAAAUCAACAUAGAGAUGAUGGUGAAAAAGGAGAUCCAGGAGAAGAGGGAAAGCAUGGCAAAGUGGGACGCAUGGGGCCGAAAGGAAUUAAAGGAGAACUGGGUGAUAUGGGAGAUCAGGGCAAUAUUGGCAAGACUGGGCCCAUUGGGAAGAAGGGUGACAAAGGGGAAAAAGGUUUGCUUGGAAUACCUGGAGAAAAAGGCAAAGCAGGUACUGUCUGUGAUUGUGGAAGAUACCGGAAAUUUGUUGGACAACUGGAUAUUAGUAUUGCUCGGCUCAAGACAUCUAUGAAGUUUGUCAAGAAUGUGAUAGCAGGGAUUAGGGAAACUGAAGAGAAAUUCUACUACAUCGUGCAGGAAGAGAAGAACUACAGGGAAUCCCUAACCCACUGCAGGAUUCGGGGUGGAAUGCUAGCCAUGCCCAAGGAUGAAGCUGCCAACACACUCAUCGCUGACUAUGUUGCCAAGAGUGGCUUCUUUCGGGUGUUCAUUGGCGUGAAUGACCUUGAAAGGGAGGGACAGUACAUGUUCACAGACAACACUCCACUGCAGAACUAUAGCAACUGGAAUGAGGGGGAACCCAGCGACCCCUAUGGUCAUGAGGACUGUGUGGAGAUGCUGAGCUCUGGCAGAUGGAAUGACACAGAGUGCCAUCUUACCAUGUACUUUGUCUGUGAGUUCAUCAAGAAGAAAAAGUAACUUCCCUCAUCCUACGUAUUUGCUAUUUUCCUGUGACCGUCAUUACAGUUAUUGUUAUCCAUCCUUUUUUUCCUGAUUGUACUACAUUUGAUCUGAGUCAACAUAGCUAGAAAAUGCUAAACUGAGGUAUGGAGCCUCCAUCAUCAUGCUCUUUUGUGAUGAUUUUCAUAUUUUCACACAUGGUAUAUUAUUGACCCAAUAACUCGCCAGGUUACAUGGGUCUUGAGAGAGAAUUUUAAUUACUAAUUGUGCACGAGAUAGUUGGUUGUCUAUAUGUCAAAUGAGUUGUUCUCUUGGUAUUUGCUCUACCAUCUCUCCCUAGAGCACUCUGUGUCUAUCCCAGUGGAUAAUUUCCCAGUUUACUGGUGAUGAUUAGGAAGGUUGUUGAUGGUUAGGCUAACCUGCCCUGGCCCAAAGCCAGACAUGUACAAGGGCUUUCUGUGAGCAAUGAUAAGAUCUUUGAAUCCAAGAUGCCCAGAUCUUUUACCAGUCACACCCUAUGGCCAUGGCUAUACUUGGAAGUUCUCCUUGUUGGCACAGACAUAGAAAUGCUUUAACCCCAAACCUUUAUAUGGGGGACUUCUAGCUUUGUGUCUUGUUUCAGACCAUGUGGAAUGAUAAAUACUCUUUUUGUGCUUCUGAUCUAUCGAUUUCACUAACAUAUACCAAGUAGGUGCUUUGAACCCCUUUCUGUAGGCUCACACCUUAAUCUCAGGCCCCUAUAUAGUCACACUUUGAUUUAAGAAAAAUGGAGCUCUUGAAAUCAAAAGAAAAAAAUGGGGAAUUGUUCACAAACAAUACUGGUUAUAGUUCUCUUGCUAAAUUGCCCACUGCUAUUAACUUAACUUCAUUUUUAUUUAUCUUAGGUUUACCUGCAUCAAUUUUAUUCACCUUAGGCAUAGGGAAUGAGGGAAGGAGUUUGUGAAGCCUUAAGAAAAUUCUGGAAGCUUCAAAGUGCUACCAACAUCAUCUCCAGGCCCCCUCAUCCUUGCCUCUAACAUAUCACUAAUGGUGACAUUUCAUGGGAGGCCUUUUACUCUUCAUAAAUAUAUGUCAUAGAAAUCCUACUGGAGAUGUCCCUUCUAAUACUCUGGCAUCACAGAAAUGUGUGAGGCACAGAAUUCGGAACAUGCUUAGAACUCACAUUUACUGAGCUGGUAAAAUUCUACCUUGAACUGUAGAUCAAACCUCAAAGCAGCUUUCACUUGGAAUUUAAAAAUAAACAGUUCAAAGAUACUCUAGAUUAUCACCCUAUAAACUUCUACUCCAGUUAUGGUUUCUGACAUAUGAUUAGACUGUUUCAAAUGCUGGCAAAAUGGUUAAUGAAGUAAGAGAAACAGAUCAACAACAUAUGUUCACCUUAAACCAUCUGUUCAUGAUUUCACCCGUGACUAACUGGUUAUGAGAUAGGACUUAAUUAGGUUAUUUCUGUGGGUUCAACAAGGGCCAUAAACUCAGAUCCUACAGGGGCCAGGCAGAUGACUUACCUAAAUGAAGUGGAACACGUGGGGACCCUAGUGCACUGAGCACAGCUUGCCCUUCCAAAGGAGCCAGCUGCUCCUCAGUGGCUGCUGCUGGUGCUAGGGAGGACCCAAUCUUGCUAAAUGUGCUGAUAUUUCAAGAGAAGUCAGAAAGCUGGGACUUUGUAACAUAAGCUCAUAUUUUAAUAUGUUGGCAACUAAUUAAUUUUUAACCCAAAUUUUAAGUGGGUUAAAAAUUAAUUAAAAUUAAAGAUUUGAGGUCAAAAGUCUUCUAGCUAAAGUUGUGAUCAUUUCAUUUCUUACUUCUGGAGGAAGGUUCAGAAGGUUCUAACCAAAUAGAAUGUCAUUAGGAUAUGAUGACAUGAAAGUCAAGAUAUCCCAUUAAUACCAUAUUCAAUUCAGCUUAAUAAUAGGAAUUUGUUAUAUGUUUGACAUUUAUCAGGUUACUAGUUAAACUCUUUUGAGAUGAUAGUACAUGACACUUUAAAGGCAGAAAAGCUUAAUAAAAAUUACAAAGUAGGACAUCAAACGCCAGUAUCCUUGGAUAGAAAGCCAUCCCAGAUCAUGAGGAAUGAAAACCUAGAAACACCUGUAGGAAAAUAAAGCUCAUAUGUAAGAAGAGAGGAAGGAGAGACAUGCAGCAAAUGUUGCCUACGGGCAACUUCAUGUUAAGGAUCCAUGUUCUGAUUUGUUCUAAGCCCCCAAAGUAUGAGUAUUUAUUGUGUGCACUGUUAGUGCUAUUAUUAUUUACUGUGAAUGUUAUAAUAAUAGUUCUCUCAAUGA